AGUGAGGGAGCAGUGGCUGGGGUGGCCCAGCUUCAAAGUCUCUGUCCUCUUGAAAAAAGGUGGUCGGGGGACAUUGACCCACCAGCCCCGCAGGCUACUGCCUGCAAACAAGAACCCCUCAUCUGCCACGCACGUUCUUAAUGUAUCUAUAGUCUGCCUGAUGCCACAAAGGAGUCCAGGGUCUCGCUCUGUCACACAGGCUGGAGUGCAGUGGUGUGAUCUUGGCUCAUCGUAACCUCCACCUCCCGGGUUCAAGUGAUUCUCAUGCCUCAGCCUCCCGAGUAGCUGGGAUUACAGGUGGUGACUUCCAAGAGUGACUCCGUCGGAGGAAAAUGACUCCCCAGUCGCUGCUGCAGACGACACUGUUCCUGCUGAGUCUGCUCUUCCUGGUCCAAGCCUCUGCCUCCUCAGGUGCCCACGGCAGGGGCCACAGGGAAGACUUUCGCUUCUGCAGCCAGCGGAACCAGACACACAGGAGCAGCCUCCACUACAAACCCACACCAGACCUGCGCAUCUCCAUCGAGAACUCCGAAGAGGCCCUCACAGUCCAUGCCCCUUUCCCUGCAGCCCACCCUGCUUCCCGAUCCUUCCCUGACCCCAGGGGCCUCUACCACUUCUGCCUCUACUGGAACCGACAUGCUGGGAGAUUACAUCUUCUCUAUGGCAAGCGUGACUUCUUGCUGAGUGACAAAGCCUCUAGCCUCCUCUGCUUCCAGCACCAGGAGGAGAGCCUGGCUCAGGGCCCCCCGCUGUUAGCCACUUCUGUCACCUCCUGGUGGAGCCCUCAGAACAUCAGCCUGCCCAGUGCCGCCAGCUUCACCUUCUCCUUCCACAGUCCUCCCCACACGGCCGCUCACAAUGCCUCGGUGGACAUGUGCGAGCUCAAAAGGGACCUCCAGCUGCUCAGCCAGUUCCUGAAGCAUCCCCAGAAGGCCUCAAGGAGGCCCUCGGCUGCCCCCGCCAGCCAGCAGUUGCAGAGCCUGGAGUCGAAACUGACCUCUGUGAGAUUCAUGGGGGACAUGGUGUCCUUCGAGGAGGACCGGAUCAACGCCACGGUGUGGAAGCUCCAGCCCACAGCCGGCCUCCAGGACCUGCACAUCCACUCCCGGCAGGAGGAGGAGCAGAGCGAGAUCAUGGAGUACUCGGUGCUGCUGCCUCGAACACUCUUCCAGAGGACGAAAGGCCGGAGCGGGGAGGCUGAGAAGAGACUCCUCCUGGUGGACUUCAGCAGCCAAGCCCUGUUCCAGGACAAGAAUUCCAGCCAAGUCCUGGGUGAGAAGGUCUUGGGGAUUGUGGUACAGAACACCAAAGUAGCCAACCUCACGGAGCCCGUGGUGCUCACUUUCCAGCACCAGCUACAGCCGAAGAAUGUGACUCUGCAAUGUGUGUUCUGGGUUGAAGACCCCACAUUGAGCAGCCCGGGGCAUUGGAGCAGUGCUGGGUGUGAGACCGUCAGGAGAGAAACCCAAACAUCCUGCUUCUGCAACCACUUGACCUACUUUGCAGUGCUGAUGGUCUCCUCGGUGGAGGUGGACGCCGUGCACAAGCACUACCUGAGCCUCCUCUCCUACGUGGGCUGUGUCGUCUCUGCCCUGGCCUGCCUUGUCACCAUUGCCGCCUACCUCUGCUCCAGGGUGCCCCUGCCGUGCAGGAGGAAACCUCGGGACUACACCAUCAAGGUGCACAUGAACCUGCUGCUGGCCGUCUUCCUGCUGGACACGAGCUUCCUGCUCAGCGAGCCGGUGGCCCUGACAGGCUCUGAGGCUGGCUGCCGAGCCAGUGCCAUCUUCCUGCACUUCUCCCUGCUCACCUGCCUUUCCUGGAUGGGCCUCGAGGGGUACAACCUCUACCGACUCGUGGUGGAGGUCUUUGGCACCUAUGUCCCUGGCUACCUACUCAAGCUGAGCGCCAUGGGCUGGGGCUUCCCCAUCUUUCUGGUGACGCUGGUGGCCCUGGUGGAUGUGGACAACUAUGGCCCCAUCAUCUUGGCUGUGCAUAGGACUCCAGAGGGCGUCAUCUACCCUUCCAUGUGCUGGAUCCGGGACUCCCUGGUCAGCUACAUCACCAACCUGGGCCUCUUCAGCCUGGUGUUUCUGUUCAACAUGGCCAUGCUAGCCACCAUGGUGGUGCAGAUCCUGCGGCUGCGCCCCCACACCCAAAAGUGGUCACAUGUGCUGACACUGCUGGGCCUCAGCCUGGUCCUUGGCCUGCCCUGGGCCUUGAUCUUCUUCUCCUUUGCUUCUGGCACCUUCCAGCUUGUCGUCCUCUACCUUUUCAGCAUCAUCACCUCCUUCCAAGGCUUCCUCAUCUUCAUCUGGUACUGGUCCAUGCGGCUGCAGGCCCGGGGUGGCCCCUCCCCUCUGAAGAGCAACUCAGACAGCGCCAGGCUCCCCAUCAGCUCGGGCAGCACCUCGUCCAGCCGCAUCUAGGCCUCCAGCCCACCUGCCCAUGUGAUGAAGCAGAGAUUCGGCCUCGUCGCACACUGCCUGUGGCCCCCGAGCCCGGCCCAGCCCCAGGCCAGUCAGCCGCAGACUUUGGAAAGCCCAACGACCAUGGAGAGAUGGGCCGUUGCCAUGGUGGACGGACUCCCGGGCUGGGCUUUUGAAUUGGCCUUGGGGACUACUCGGCUCUCACUCAGCUCCCACGGGACUCAGAAGUGCGCCGCCAUGCUGCCUAGGGUACUGUCCCCACAUCUGUCCCAACCCAGCUGGAGGCCUGGUCUCUCCUUACAACCCCUGGGCCCAGCCCUCAUUGCUGGGGGCCAGGCCUUGGAUCUUGAGGGUCUGGCACAUCCUUAAUCCUGUGCCCCUGCCUGGGACAGAAAUGUGGCUCCAGUUGCUCUGUCUCUCGUGGUCACCCUGAGGGCACUCUGCAUCCUCUGUCAUUUUAACCUCAGGUGGCACCCAGGGCGAAUGGGGCCCAGGGCAGACCUUCAGGGCCAGAGCCCUGGCGGAGGAGAGGCCCUUUGCCAGGAGCACAGCAGCAGCUCGCCUACCUCUGAGCCCAGGCCCCCUCCCUCCCUCAGCCCCCCAGUCCUCCCUCCAUCUUCCCUGGGGUUCUCCUCCUCUCCCAGGGCCUCCUUGCUCCUUCGUUCACAGCUGGGGGUCCCCGAUUCCAAUGCUGUUUUUUGGGGAGUGGUUUCCAGGAGCUGCCUGGUGUCUGCUGUAAAUGUUUGUCUACUGCACAAGCCUCGGCCUGCCCCUGAGCCAGGCUCGGUACCGAUGCGUGGGCUGGGCUAGGUCCCUCUGUCCAUCUGGGCCUUUGUAUGAGCUGCAUUGCCCUUGCUCACCCUGACCAAGCACACGCCUCAGAGGGGCCCUCAGCCUCUCCUGAAGCCCUCUUGUGGCAAGAACUGUGGACCAUGCCAGUCCCGUCUGGUUUCCAUCCCACCACUCCAAGGACUGAGACUGACCUCCUCUGGUGACACUGGCCUAGGGCCUGACACUCUCCUAAGAGGUUCUCUCCAAGCCCCCAAAUAGCUCCAGGCGCCCUCGGCCGCCCAUCAUGGUUAAUUCUGUCCAACAAACACACACGGGUAGAUUGCUGGCCUGUUGUAGGUGGUAGGGACACAGAUGACCGACCUGGUCACUCCUCCUGCCAACAUUCAGUCUGGUAUGUGAGGCGUGCGUGAAGCAAGAACUCCUGGAGCUACAGGGACAGGGAGCCAUCAUUCCUGCCUGGGAAUCCUGGAAGACUUCCUGCAGGAGUCAGCGUUCAAUCUUGACCUUGAAGAUGGGAAGGAUGUUCUUUUUACGUACCAAUUCUUUUGUCUUUUGAUAUUAAAAAGAAGUACAUGUUCAUUGUAGAGAAUUUGGAAACUGUAGAAGAGAAUCAAGAAGAAAAAUAAAAAUCAGCUGUUGUAAUCACCUAGCAAACUGGCGUAAGCAUUUUGGGUCAUUUCCUUCUGAGCUUUUUCCUGUGCUUCUAUUGAAAGAGUCACUGAUACUAAUACAAAUACCUUGGGGCCAAUCAGGAAACAUGAAAGAGAGAAGAGGGCUGUGUGUGAAGAAAAAAAAAAAAUCGACUGCUGGAAACCUCAUCAACCAGGGCACAGGGGAAGAUAAAUGGCAACUUGGUGUCUGUGCUGGGGAGGCAAUGGGGAGUGGUGGGGCCUGUGGCGAACUGGAGACUCCCAACCCCAUGCUGAGAGCGUGGCUGCUCAUCAGCUCCAGCUGGUCACUACCUUGCAGGGAUGAGGGCCCAUGUAGCCAGACCACCUGCCUUUUAUGAGAAAUGGGAAAUCCAGACUGUGGUUUGACAUCCCCUGAUUUUAAAAUUUUGGCGAAUCCAAAACAUUUUCUGGCCAAAGAGAUUACAGUCAAAAGCUGCCUGGUCCUGGGAUUUAUGCAACCAGUUUACUGAUCACUCUGCAGCAGGUGGGCUGCAAGAAUUAAAUCACUGGACUUCUCUCCCA